AGGCAGUUGCGGGUUGCAGGAGUUCAGGAAAGGAGGUGGGACUAGAGUCAACCUGGAAUAGCUCUACAGUAACAAUGGCAGCCUUUUUGUUGCUGGGACAUCCAUACAGGCAACUUAGCUGGUGAAAGGACUCUGGAUUGGUUGGCAGUCUGCUUUUUUUUUUCCAAGGUGAUCACUUUACUGUAGAAGAAAUGAGGUUAACAGAAAAGAGUGAGGGAGAACAACAACUCAAGCCCAACAACUCUAAUGCACCCAAUGAAGAUCAAGAAGAAGAAAUCCAACAGUCAGAACAGCAUACUCCAGCAAGGCAGCGAACACAAAGAGCAGACACACAGCCAUCCAGAUGUCGAUUGCCUUCACGUAGGACACCUACAACAUCCAGCGACAGAACGAUCAACCUUCUUGAAGUCCUUCCGUGGCCUACUGAGUGGAUUUUCAACCCCUAUCGAUUGCCUGCUCUUUUUGAGCUUUAUCCUGAAUUUCUUCUGGUGUUUAAAGAAGCCUUCCAUGACAUAUCCCAUUGUCUGAAAGCCCAGAUGGAAAAGAUCGGACUGCCCAUCAUACUCCACCUCUUCGCACUCUCCACCCUCUACUUCUACAAGUUUUUCCUUCCUACAAUUCUUUCCCUUUCUUUCUUUAUUCUUCUUGUACUUCUGCUUCUGCUUUUUAUUAUUGUCUUCAUUCUGAUCUUCUUCUGAUUCUUUUGUUUCAAUAAACAGCAAUGAGCAUGAA